GCGGUCUGCGGCGCGGAGCCGAGUGGGCUGCGGGGAUGCGGGGGACCAGCUGCGUGGGCGGCGGCGCCGAGAGCCCCGGAGGCGCGGGGCUGAGCGAGGGCCCGCGGGGGCGCUGGCUGCGCUUGGCUCCGGUAUGCGCCUACUUCCUCUGCGUCUCGCUAGCUGCCGUGCUGCUCGCCGUGUACUACGGUCUCAUCUGGGUACCCACGCGGUCUCCCGCGGCACCCGCCGGCCCACAGCCCAGCGCGCCGUCCCCUCCGUGUGCUGCCCGCCCGGGCGUGCCGCCUGUCCCGGCGCCCGCCGCUGCCUCCCUCUCCUGCCUCCUGGGAGUCCCCGGCGGGCCGCGACCCCAGCUCCAGCUGCCGCUGAGCCGCCGCCGCCGCUACAGCGACCCUGACCGCCGUCCGAGCCGCCAGACACCCAGAGAGACGCCAGAGGCCGCGGAGGGGCGAAGACCCGGGUAACUCUCCCUUCCACCCCAACCCGGAUCGCCAGCCCUCGAGAGCUCUGUGCUCCACGCCGAGGAUGCACCGUCUCUGGAUUGGUCCGGCCUUCUUCCUAAUGACAUCGCUCAGCGUCUCUGGAGCCGUCAUCCCGCGGAAUGGGGGCCCAGGGGGUGUCAGCUCGGGGCCUUGCCUCUUGCAGCUACUCUGUGGUCAGGCCGGGUCCUCCACCAUCAGGAAGAUCCCAUCCUGAGCUCUGUCUCCUGCCCCUCCUGCUGUGGGAUGCUGAGCACAGAGCCCACAGCCCAUCUGCCUCUUCACCUCCCUGAAUCCGUGUCCAUCUGCAAUAAACGACAGCCUCGGCUGCCUCGUGCUGUGUCUGUCCUGUUGUCUGCA